GUCUCGCCAUGCUGCUCCUGGGCCUGCUGCUGCUGCUGCCCCUGCUGGCUGGCGCCCGCCUGCUGUGGAACUGGUGGAAGCUCCGGAGCCUCCACCUCCCGCCUCUUGCCCCGGGCUUCUUGCACCUGCUGCAGCCCGACCUCCCCAUCUAUCUGCUUGGCCUGACUCAGAAAUUCGGGCCCAUCUACAGGCUCCACCUUGGGCUGCAAGAUGUGGUGGUGCUGAACUCCAAGAGGACCAUUGAGGAAGCCAUGGUCAAAAAGUGGGCAGACUUUGCUGGCAGACCUGAGCCACUUACCUCCCCCACCUCCUCCUGCAGACAAGCUGGUGUCUAGGAACUACCCGGACCUGUCCUUGGGAGACUACUCCCUGCUCUGGAAAGCCCACAAGAAGCUCACCCGCUCAGCCCUGCUGCUGGGCAUCCGUGACUCCAUGGAGCCAGUGGUGGAGCAGCUGACCCAGGAGUUCUGUGAGCGCAUGAGAGCCCAGCCCGGCACCCCUGUGGCCAUUGAGGAGGAAUUCUCUCUCCUCACCUGCAGCAUCAUCUGUUACCUCACCUUCGGAGACAAGAUCAAGGACGACAACUUAAUGCCUGCCUAUUACAAAUGUAUCCAGGAGGUGUUAAAAACCUGGAGCCACUGGUCCAUCCAAAUUGUGGACGUGAUUCCCUUUCUCAGGUUCUUCCCCAAUCCAGGUCUCCGGAGGCUGAAGCAGGCCAUAGAGAAGAGGGAUCACAUCGUGGAGAUGCAGCUGAGGCAGCACAAGGAGAGCCUCGUGGCAGGCCAGUGGAGGGACAUGAUGGACUACAUGCUCCAAGGGGUGGCGCAGCCGAGCAUGGAAGAGGGCUCUGGACAGCUCCUGGAAGGGCACGUGCACAUGGCUGCAGUGGACCUCCUGAUCGGUGGCACUGAGACCACAGCAAACACCCUCUCCUGGGCCGUGGUUUUUUUGCUUCACCACCCUGAGAUUCAGCAGCGACUGCAGGAGGAGCUAGACCACGAACUGGGCCCUGGUGCCUCCAGCUCCCGGGUCCCCUACAAGGACCGUGCACGGCUGCCCUUGCUCAAUGCCACCAUCGCCGAGGUGCUGCGCCUGCGGCCCGUUGUGCCCUUAGCCUUGCCCCACCGCACCACACGGCCCAGCAGCAUCUCCGGCUACGACAUCCCUGAGGGCACAGUCAUCAUUCCGAACCUCCAAGGCGCCCACCUGGAUGAGACGGUCUGGGAGAGGCCACAUGAGUUCUGGCCUGAUCGCUUCCUGGAGCCAGGCAAGAACUCCAGAGCUCUGGCCUUCGGCUGCGGUGCCCGCGUGUGCCUGGGCGAGCCGCUGGCGCGCCUGGAGCUCUUCGUGGUGCUGACCCGACUGCUGCAGGCCUUCACGCUGCUGCCCUCCGGGGACGCCCUGCCCUCCCUGCAGCCCCUGCCCCACUGCAGUGUCAUCCUCAAGAUGCAGCCUUUCCAAGUGCGGCUGCAGCCCCGGGGGAUGGGGGCCCACAGCCCGGGCCAGAGCCAGUGAUGGGGCAGGACCGAUGCCAGCCGGGUACCUCAGUUUCUCCUUUAUUGCUCCCGUACGAACCCCUCCCCUCCCCCCUGUAAACACAGUGCUGCGAGAUCGCUGGCAGAGAAGGCUUCCUCCAGCGGCUGGGUGGUGAAGGACCCUGGCUCUUCUCUCGGGGCGACCCCUCAGUGCUCGGCAGUCAUACUGGGGUGCGAGAGAGGUGGGCAGCAGCUCAGCCUCCCCCCGCUGGGGAGCGAAAGUUUCUUGGUCUCAGCUUCAUUUCCGUGAAGGGCACCGAGAACUCGAAGCCCUUCCAGUGGUACCAGCUCACUCCCUGGGAAAGGGGUUGUCAAGAGAGAGUCAAAGCCGGAUGUCCCAUCUGCUCUUCCCGUUCCCCUUAAGGAGGUAGCUCCCAGCACUCAACCAACCUCCCCGCAGAGCUCCCUUCCUGACCCUCCGCUGCAGAGGAUUGAGGCUUAAUUCUGAGCUGGCCCUUUCCAGCCAAUAAAUCAACUCCAGCUCCCUC